GAGGCGGAAGCGGCGCUUGCUUCAGGUGGAGUCUGUUAGUUUUUGAGAAAGAGUUAGGGCGAGUUUAAGGCACUGUGGCAGCUGUGAGAUAAAGUCUGGUUCCUCCCCAGCUGGCUCAGGAAAUGUUCGCGGAUACAACGGCGGCCCCCUCUGGGCAUACCUGCCUGUGGAGCGGAGAGUGGACGGUGUGAGGGGGACCGGGAGAGGCACCAAAUCUGGCCUGGGGGCCCGAGAAGCUUCCUCUCAGUGACCACAAUAUGAAUGGGAACAGCAAGAUGGCAAAAGCUUGCUGAGUGGUACAGCGCCAGCCUGGGUAGUGGCCUCCCCAGCAAGUUGCAUGUCACUAGCUUCCUGUGGCUGUCACUCCUGGGCCCAGGCACCUCCGAAGAUCAGCACCUCCUCAUGGGCUCAAGCGAGGACAGGAGCCCGUCACCCAUGAGCUCUCAAGGGCAGAGCCACUGUCCUGUCUCGAUGGCUCCACCGUGACUCCAGUGGACUUUGGACAGUGGGGAGCAGGCCCAACAGGGCCACUCGGAUGUGGUCACUCUGGAUUUGGGUGGAUCAGCACCAAGCUAGACUCAUCCCCAGCCCCCAGGUGCUGUUGCUGCUCCUGCGUGAGGCCCCAUCCACAGCUGCAGCUGUGGCAGGGUGGCUAGUGGUGGCCAGCAUGGCCCUGCUGCAGCUCCACGCUGUGGGGGGCGUGGCCCUGACCAGCAGCCACCCCUCCAUGUGGGCCACAGGGGAGGAGCUUAGGAAGCCGCCUUGGCAAGGUUCCGCAGGCUCUGCGUCUGGUGUGGAAGAGCUCACGGGGAAGCACUCCUGCCCAGGACCCGAGGAGCCGGCCACCGUUCAGAAGGCCCCAGCUUGAAGGCCUGGAGAGCCGCCCAGCAGCACAACACAGGGAAGCUUGGGGAGGUUUAAUUUAACCUGAGAAGGCUGCAGAUCCUCGGGGUUGGUGUAAAAACACCUCAUCCUGAUCUGAGAAGGCGGUCAGCUUUUCUCCUCGUUGCCGUUGGCUGCCAGCACCCAUUCUCUGUGGAUGUGAAAAUCCCAGAAGGGCUGGGCUUCCUUCUUGGGCAUUCCCCAGGCCUAUCUCCAGAGUGGGGCCCAGCAUGGGAGGAUUGUACCCCACUCACUCCCCUGAUGUGGGGCUUGGACCUACAGCUCGACAGCACCCAUGGAAUGUGGGCAGAAGCGACAGCAGCCAGCUCCGCCUUGGCCUUAGGGCGGCACGUGUUCUGCUUGUGCCCUGGGAGCCUCCACCUUCCACACUGUGGGAAGAGGGUGCCCAGGGAGCUGCAGUCUCUCCAGCCCAGCCCCAGGACGAGGCCCAGGCAGCAGAGCCACCCCAGCAGACCUGGCAGUGUGAGAGAAAUGCAUGUGUAUACACUGAGUUUGCAGGUGGCUGUUACAUGGCAGCAUUGACUGACACAGACAGAAAAGAGAUCCACGAGGGAGAAGUGAGAGUGCUGGAGACUCCACAAGCCACAGGCUGCAGGGGCAGGAUGGCUUCUUAGAAGGUGAAAUGAUUGUUCUGGGAAUCUAUCAGAGGAAGACAUAGAGGCUCCAGACGGUUGAAGGCCCAACAGUGAUCCCAGACGGGCCCCAUGUCAGACCAGGCUCCUCCAGGGCUGUGCUGCCCUCACCAAAGCCCGUCCUGAGGGCAGCCACACAGCAGGCAGCACUCGCCAUUUGUACAAGCGAGGCCCAAGUUCCAGCCUUCCUUCUGGCAGGUAGAGGAAGCAGGGGCACUAUGCCUGGGAGUUCCUGAAAGCAGAUGGGGCAGCAUUUGGUCAAGAGCCAGGAGGGGAUGACAGACCAGAGGGGAACCCUCGUCCCACGUGCUGAGCACACGUAGGGGGUUGGGCACUUGCUCUGUGAGCUAUAAUUGGUGUCCCUGUGCCCCGCCGGAAGCUGCACCAGGCAGUUUCUUGGUGGAGGACAGUGGCCGCCCUCUAGCUUUACUCCCUUCCCCGUGAUGGGUCGCUGUCAGAUGUGUGUCCAGGAAAGGCAAACACCAAAGGCAGAGGACUAGUCCCUACACCGAAUACUCCGGUGGCCUUGCUUGGGGGCUGGGUUUUGACGUGCUGGAGGCUGUCCUAGACUUAGAGAUUAAAAACAGGGAAGAACCAUUGCUGAAACCUUUGGAAAAGCCUGCAAUGGGGCCUCUGGCAGCCUGAGGAGUGGUGGUGUUUCCAUCUGGUAGACGCCGUCUCAAUAGGAGGGACAGAUGAGUGCACCAGUGCUGCCAGCCAGAGGCGUCUGUUGGCGUGUCUUUAUGGAAUGGGGUGCCAGUCUUGUGGAGGGUGGUUUACCUUCCUGUUUCUAGUCCCCACUGGGCCUGCCUUCUGCUUCAUGGCCAGCUGGCCAGACCGAGCACUUUCCUGACUUUCGACCUUGGCCCCUGCUGACUCUUGCCGUUGAGGCCUCCUGCAGACCCCAUUUGUAUUCAUUUCCUGCAGUUCUCAUACCUGAAUCCCGCCUGGACUUCUGCCAAGCCUUCCAGGCCCUCCUCCCCCAGGGGGACCACAGAUGCUACGUGCAGGGCUGUCCUUGGAGGGCCAGCACAGCCCCUUCCAAGUGGGCAAGACCCAGGGGUGGCUCAAAAGAUAGCUGUGCCCUAGCCCUGGAACCUCUGAAUGUUGAUUUUUGUAGCAAAAAAGGACUUGCAGAUGUGAGUAAAGGCUGUUGAGAUAAGGACAUCCUCCCUGCUCUCUGGGAGGACCCCAAAUGCAGGUGCACAGAUCUUAAGAAGAAGAGGCAGAGACUGGGGUGAUGCAGCCACAACUAAGGAAAGCCAAGGAUUGCUGGCAGCCUGCAGAAACUGGAGGGCAAGGAGCAUCCCCCAACCGCCCGGAGCCUCCAGGAGGCGCAAGGUCCUACUGACUCCCUGACUUCAGACGUCCAGUCUCCGGAAUUUUGAGAGGAUCCAUUUCUGUUAUUUUAAGCAACCAAACUUGUGGUAGUUUCACCAGUCUCAGGAAAUGAAUACGAAUGGAAAGUCAAAGAUUCCAAGAAAUGAGUGGCGGGGUGCGGUGGCUCACACUUGUAAUCCCAGCAUUUGCGGGAAGAUUGCUUGGGCUCAGGACUUGGAGACCUUGUGUCUGUGAGAAACUUAAAAAAUAGGCUGGGUGCGAUGGCUCACGCCUGUAAUCCCAGCACUUUGGGAGGCCGAGGCAGGCGGAUCACAAGGUCACGAGUUUGAGACCAGUGUGACCAACAUGGUGAAACCCUGUCUCUACUAAAAAUACAAAAAUUAGCCGGGUGUGGUGGUGCGUGCCUGUAAUCCCAGCUACUCGGGAGGCUGAGGCAGAAGAAUUGCUUGAACCCAGGAAGCAGAGGUUGCAGUGAGCCGAGAUAGUAUUACUGCACUCCAGGCUGGGCAGCAGAGCAAGAUUCCGCCUCAAAAAAAAAAAAAAAAAAAAAAAAAAAAAAAAAAACUGAGCAUGGUAGCAUGCACCUGUGGUCCUGGCUACGCCGGAGGAUUGCCUGAAGCCAGGAGUUCAAGACCAGUCUGGACAAAAGAGCAAGACCCCAUCUCUACCAAAAAAAUUUAAAAAUUAGCCAGGCAUGGUGCCGUACCCAUAGUCUUAGCUACUCAGGAGGCUGAGGAGGGAGGAUUAUCUGAGCCCUGGCGGUUGAGGCUAUAAUGAGCCAUGAUUGUGCCACUGCACUCCAGCCUUGGCAACACAGUGUGAGACCCUGUCUCAAAAACAAUAAAAACCCAAAACAAAAGAACCAAGAAAUUACUGGACCUGAGGCCUGGCCUUUAGCUGCUGCCCUGCCCUUGUGACCUGGUCACUCGGGAUCCCCUGGGCCUAAACACACAGCCUAUUGUCUACCUCAAGAAGGCUCCCCACUGCUUGGCUGGCAAUUGGGGUGGGCUUUGCAGGCCCCACCUGUCCUGGCCCCACGGCGCUGGUGCUGCAGGCCCCCACCACUGCUUGUUCCGAGCUCCCCAGCCUCCUGCAGAGUUGCCUGCACCUGAUGGCGAUGAAUCAGGAAGGCAGGCGUGUCCUGGGCCACAGAGCAGUCAUGGCUGUCAGCCACCAGGGGGCUCCAUUUGCAACUUUGGAUGUGGCUUUGGCCUCUUUGUCCAAAGUGACCUUGGGGCCCCCAGACAAGAGACAGGGAGACUGGAGCCCAGCCCCACCCUCCCGCACAUACCUGGCCCAUCCCUGCCCUAUCCUGGAAGAUGGGGGCCACCACACGUGCAAGGGACACGGGAUAGGAACCUUUGGCCUUGUUAUCAGACAUUUUAAAACUAAGUGCAAACGUGAUUAUCAGGUGCAGUUUUUACAGCAGCAAGAAACCUGUGCUUACAGAAAGAAACACGUGCUAGCAACCCACCUAUGCGGAAAGCCACACAGAGCCAUUGUUUUCUGCACUCUCAGGUGACGGCUCACAUUUGCCCCAGGGAAGGUCACAGCUGCCUGAACUUUUAAAACUCCCAGACACGCACUGCCUGUGCAGGAUCCGGAGCCCAGCAGCACUGCCAGGGCCUUGAAGUGCUUCUUCAGAGACCUUUCUUCAUAGACUACUUUUUUUUCUUUAAGCAGCAAAAGGAGAAAAUUGUCAUCAAAGGAUAUUCCAGAUUCUUGACAGCAUUCUCGUCAUCUCUGAGGACAUCACCAUCAUCUCAGGAUGAGGGGCAUGAAGCUGCUGGGGGCGCUGCUGGCACUGGCGGCCCUACUGCAGGGGGCCGUGUCCCUGAAGAUCGCAGCCUUCAACAUCCAGACAUUUGGGGAGACCAAGAUGUCCAAUGCCACCCUCGUCAGCUACAUUGUGCAGAUCCUGAGCCGCUAUGACAUCGCCCUGGUCCAGGAGGUCAGAGACAGCCACCUGACUGCCGUGGGGAAGCUGCUGGACAACCUCAAUCAGGAUGCACCAGACACCUAUCACUACGUGGUCAGUGAGCCACUGGGACGGAACAGCUAUAAGGAGCGCUACCUGUUCGUGUACAGGCCUGACCAGGUGUCUGCGGUGGACAGCUACUACUACGAUGAUGGCUGCGAGCCCUGCGGGAACGACACCUUCAACCGAGAGCCAGCCAUUGUCAGGUUCUUCUCCCGGUUCACAGAGGUCAGGGAGUUUGCCAUUGUUCCCCUGCAUGCGGCCCCGGGGGACGCAGUAGCCGAGAUCGACGCUCUCUAUGACGUCUACCUGGAUGUCCAAGAGAAAUGGGGCUUGGAGGACGUCAUGUUGAUGGGCGACUUCAAUGCGGGCUGCAGCUAUGUGAGACCCUCCCAGUGGUCAUCCAUCCGCCUGUGGACAAGCCCCACCUUCCAGUGGCUGAUCCCCGACAGCGCUGACACCACAGCUACACCCACGCACUGUGCCUAUGACAGGAUCGUGGUUGCAGGGAUGCUGCUCCGAGGCGCCGUUGUUCCCGACUCGGCUCUUCCCUUUAACUUCCAGGCUGCCUAUGGCCUGAGUGACCAACUGGUAUGUGUCCUCCCUUGCACAGCCACAUGAGGAUGGGACACAGGAGCUCAGUUCUCAGUUCACACCUGCUCUGGAGCAGGGCUGGGAGAAAGACACGGCCUUCCUGCCUCAGCGGCACUCCCGAGCAACACGUGCCGAGCAGGGACCCACAGGGUCUCCACCUGACACCAAGGGCUUCUGCUGCUGCUGGAAGGACACCCAACGGGCCAGGUACUGGGAGCCACCAGCUGGCCAGCCUGUUAGGGACACUGCGGCCAAGUGGUGGUCCAUCCCCGGGAAAGCCUCACCUUCACGUUGGUGACACGCGACCCCAGCACAUUUCUCAUCCAGGCCAUGAGCUCCUCCGUCUCCUUCUCUGAUAGGCACUCGGCGGCUGCGGAAGAGCAGGCGACAGGGAGCUCAGGCCUGCAUCCCAACUCCCCGGCUUCCAUGGGGGCCACGCAGCAUGCUUCCAGCUCCCACCUCCUCUCCCACCAGGAUGGAGACACAAGCUAGCAAGAUGCUUUUCAUCUAAAAGUAAAACCUCAAAGGAUGCUUCAGGUUGCCUGAGGCCCAUACAACUUGGUUAGGGCUUUAAAAAAAUACACAGCCUCUCAAGAAGCUGGGCCAGCUCCAGAAGCCACCGUGGCAGGAGCACUGGACAGACCCCUGAUAUCUAAACCAGGAGGCACCUUCCUCCAGUCACCAGGGUGCUCCCACAAGGCUCUUCUCGGGGGUGGCUGAGCCCAGGUCAACUGACGAAAACCCAAAGGAAGCCCUCGCUGCGGGGCAGGAGAGGCGUGCGGGGAGUGGAAACCAGCCCCACGCCUAGAGAGCAGGGGAUGCCGACCUGGGGACCUGUCCUCAAACUUCUCCUCCUUGUAGUGAUCCACGACUAUGUCCGUCUCCACAGAGAUCAGCUUCUUCUUGUCAAACUCACGAAGGUGCAGCAGGGUGAGCUCAUCAAACUGCUCAAAGCAGAAGAGAACCUGCAGGUGGCCAAGAGCAGCUCCAUCAGACCCCGGGGGCCUCCAGCCACCACAGAAGAAAGGAUGAGGGCGGCAGGAGGGCUGGGGGAGCCAAGCGGGCCACACUGGGGAACACCGGGGCAGUUGGGGUUCCUAGGCCUGCAUGACAGUUACUACGACACCUGGGUCUAAGGAAGGCUCUGACUGCCUUCAAGGCAGAAGCACUCCACGCAUAAAGAAAUCCACAUGUGGCUGAGUGCAGUGGCUCACGCCUGUAAUCCCAGCACUUUGGGAGGCCAAAGCAGGCAGAUCAUGAGGUCAGGAGUUCGAGACCAACAUGGUGAAAUGCCGUCUCUAUUAAAAAUACAAAAAUUUGCUGGGUGUGGUGGUGUGCACCUGUAGUCCCAGCUACUCAGGAGGCUGAGGCAGGAGAAUGACCUGAACCCAGGAGGCGGAAGUUGCAGUGAGCCGAGAUCGCACCACUGCACUCUAGCCUGGGCGAGAGAGCAAGACUCCAUCUCAAAAAAACAAAAAACAAACAAAAAAAACCACAUGUGACCUCCAAGUGGGAAACAGCCGUCACAGUCGGUCCGGCCUCUGUGCCCGUGACCCUGACCCACUGUGCAGCCCUGCCCGGAGUCUUGGGCAGGUUCACCCAGCACAGAGCUGAGAAGGUCAAGACCCUCCCCAGGUUGCAGCCCCCGGAGCCCGCCCCACCCACCGCUCACCCACCUCUGUGUCUUUCUUCUUCAUGGCCUCAUAGUAGGGUGAGUGCUCUGCCAGGUGACGGUUGGGGGCGCACAGGUAGUAGAUGUUGCGGGUGCCGGCCCGCAUGCGGCUGGCGUAUUCUGAGAGGCUGGUUAGCUGCCCGGAGGGCAGCGCCGAGGACUCGUAGCGCAGCAGCUUUGCUAUGUCCUCCUAGAAGGGACGGGGCAGGUCACCACUUAUUCCAGGCCCAUGGGCUCAAUGUUGCCCAACUAACUGGGCGCAAACCCUCCGAUGCCCAUGGCCUCCUGGCACUCCAGGCUGGCCCUGACCCGAGGGACGGUAGUGGACUCGGGGGUUGUCCGAGAGCAGGCCUUGCUCUGCCCAUCAGGCCCCUUUUGGGAGCUCUGGGGGCUUAGGAAGCACCUCCUGCCCCAGGUGGCCCAGGGGCUCUCCAGGGAGCUACGCGCACCACGCCCUGGGAGGGGACCCCACCCAACAGCAGAGCCCGGCCUGGACCCAGCGUCUUCCCUCUGCCCUCAGUGACAGAGUCAGUCUCUGGUGGGCACACGGACACGGGUGAAGUCCACGGUUCCCGGCCCUCCUCACAGCUGGCUAUGGCAGAGACUGGCUUUGCCCAGUGGGUUUCAGUGGGAUUUGGAGAAGGGCCCUUAGGGGAGGGGUUUGCCCUCCUCCCCAUCAGCUGAACGCAGCUGUGACCUCUAGAGCUCAUGGGAGCUGCAGCUGGAAGGACGCAGGGGGAAAACAGAAAGAGGGAAAAGCAAGGAGCUGGACACCCAACCAGCAGGGCCCAGGCCACCCCUGCACACAUGGUGGGUCUGCAUUGAUAAGACAUGUCACACGUGCACACCUACAAAGACCUAGAAAUGUCUCUGACUCUUACCUGUGUGCUGUUAACUCAAAUGAAGAUAAAGGAGAAUGAAGAGGCCUGUGUCAGAAGCUGCCGAAGUCGGCAAACAACCAGAACACGGCCUCCUUGGGACCCCACACACGUGGUCACCCUCCUCCUGCUGCUGGGGAGAAGGGACACCAGCACGGGAUGGGCUCCUGGGAUGAAAUGUUCUGGGGUUACAGUGGAGGCAGCCACACCACACUGUGAAUGCACUAAAUGCCACUGAAUUUUACGUGUUAAAAGGUGAAUUCUGUGAAUCUGAUGCUAUGUAAGUUGUAUCUCAAUAAAAAAUGGACAAAAAA